GGUCUAAAGCGGCAGCCGCCGGGGCGCAAUGCGAGCGGCUGGCGUAGGCUUGGUGGACUGUCACUGCCACCUCUCCGCCCCGGACUUUGACCGCGAUUUGGAUGAUGUGUUGGAGAAAGCCAAGAAGGCCAAUGUUGUGGCCCUUGUGGCAGUUGCCGAACAUUCAGGAGAAUUUGAAAAGAUUAUGCAACUUUCAGAAAGGUAUAAUGGGUUUGUCCUGCCAUGCUUGGGUGUUCAUCCAGUUCAAGGACUUCCACCAGAAGACCAAAGAAGUGUCACACUAAAGGAUUUGGAUGUAGCUUUGCCCAUUAUUGAGAAUUAUAAGGAUCGGUUGUUGGCAAUUGGAGAGGUUGGACUAGAUUUCUCCCCCAGAUUUGCUGGCACUGGUGAACAGAAGGAAGAGCAAAGACAAGUCCUAAUCAGACAGAUCCAGUUAGCCAAAAGACUAAAUUUGCCUGUAAAUGUGCACUCACGCUCUGCUGGAAGACCUACCAUCAACCUUUUACAAGAGCAAGGUGCUGAGAAGGUACUGCUGCAUGCAUUUGAUGGUCGGCCAUCUGUAGCCAUGGAAGGAGUAAGAGCUGGGUACUUCUUCUCAAUUCCCCCUUCUAUCAUAAGAAGUGGACAGCUGCUUUCUCUUUUCUCUAAGAAGCAGAAACUUGUGAAACAAUUGCCUUUAACUUCUAUAUGCUUAGAAACAGAUUCACCUGCACUAGGACCAGAAAAACAGGUACGGAAUGAGCCCUGGAACAUUUCUAUUUCAGCAGAAUAUAUUGCCCAGGUGAAAGGGAUCUCAGUGGAAGAAGUUAUAGAAGUGACGACACAGAAUGCAUUAAAACUGUUUCCUAAGCUCCGACACUUGCUCCAGAAAUAGCUUCAAAACCAUCCAUUACAAAAUCGAAUCAACUGCAGGGGGCAGCAUUUGAAAAAUAGAAAUGUUCUGAUGAAGAAUCUGAACUGAAGAAGCUGUUUUAUAGGGUUAUAGAAGAUUGUAAUUGUAGAGAAAUAUUUCUCUUAGAAAUAAAACUGGGCUUGGAUCCUGAAACCCUGGGUUCUGAUUCUAGCCUUGUGCUGCUUUUCAAUUAGCCGAGUUCUGGCAGGAUAUUGGGAAAAUACUGCUACUUCUUACAUUGCCCUUUUAUAUAGAACCACCACCUGAACUGAAACCAUUGCUACUGGGAAGGGUGGCUCCCACAGGAAGAGUAUAAGCACUACUGUGAUGAGGAUGGAGUAAGCUAAAGUAUACUUUUUUUUUUUUUUGAUGGAGUUUCGCUGUUGUUGCCCAGGCUGGAGUGCAAUGGCACGAUCUUGGCUCACUGCAACCUCCACUUCCCAGGUUCUAGCGAGUCUCCUCCCUCAGCCUCCCAAGUAGCUGGGAUUACAGGCAUGUGCCACCAUGCCCAGCUAAUUUUGUAUUUUUAGUAGAGACAGGGUUUCUCCAUGUUGGUCAGGCUGGUCUCGAACUCCCGACCUCAGGUGAUCCGCCCGCCUCGGCCUCCCAAAGUGCUGGGAUUACAGGCAUGAGCCACUGCGCCAGCCUAAAGUGUGUUCUUACCACCUAUUUUUCUUCCCAUAGGAGUUAGCCAGUGAAGGGAGAAUGUCUGGUUUUCUAUGCUGUCAGAAAUCUCUUUUCUAGGUUUGUAAAAUUGAACUUUUAGUACUUCGAAUUAUUUCUCUUUAAGAUAAAAAUGCAUACGAUUUUUACACUGAUCUUAGAUUUUUGACUUAUGAGGCCAGUGGUUUAAACAAUCAUUAUUGAAUACCAAGCCCAAAAGUUUAGUUAAUACACCAAUUGUAAGUUCUGGUCUGAAUUUUGUCAACAUAUUUAGAAUGUAAAUGGCAUUAUUAAAAAUGUAUCUGAUUUCUCUGUGAACAGUAAUAUUUCAUAUUUUUAAGUUUAAAAAUGUUAGUGUAAGCCAGGCACAGUGGCAUUCACCUGUAGUGCCAACCACUCAGGAGGCUGAGAUGGGAGACCUUUUAAGCCUGAGUUUGAGUCAGGCCUGGGCAACAUAGAUGUGAGCACCUAUCUCUAAAAAUGUAAAUAAAUAAAAAUCUCAAAAAAAUUAAAAAUCUCAAGUGUAAAAACAGUUCUGUAGAUAGAUGGUAGUGAUGGUAGCACAUCAAUGUGAAGGUAUUUAAUGCCACUGAACUGUACACUUAUAACGAAUUAGGAUAAAUUUUAUGUUAUGUGUAUUUACUACAAUUUUUUAAAAAUCGUAUAUGUAGUUUAACAGGUGUGGUCAAUAUCAAAACUUAGGUAUUUAAUCUUGUUAAAUUAUAUAAGCAGAAAAUGCUGGAAAAAGUACCUGUCAUAGAAAAAAAUAAACUUCCUAAAUCAAAGUGAUUUUAUGAAAUGAUCUUCAAUAAAUAUUUUGAAAUGAAUUCAUUUAUGGAAGAAUCAAAACUAGGUCAGAUUGUCCAAACCAGACUAAGAAACUGAAUAGGGUAUUUUAUGAGGUAUUUAAUGACUCAUCAGCACCAUUUUAAAUGAAAUUCCUACAUUUAACAGGAGAUUAUAUUAAAACUGGACUUUUAAGCUCUCUUCCAA